UAAAAGACAUGUAGUCUCUGCCAACUUCACCCUCCAUGAGGCUUACUGCCUGCGGUUCCUGGUCCUGUGUCCGGAGUGUGAGGAGCCUGUCCCCAAGGAAACCAUGGAGGAGCACUGCAAGCUUGAGCACCAGCAGGUGAGGAGGCGGCAGGGAGGAUGGGGUCUGAGAGUCAAGGUGAGUGUUCAGUCCUCCCUGCAGGUGAGAUGGGGUCUGAGAGUUGGGGGACGAGGGUCUAGUCCUCCCUGCAGGUGAGAUGGGGUCUGGGAGUCAAGGCAAGUGUUCAGUCCUCUCUGCAGGAGAGAUGGGGUCUGAGAGUCAAGGCGAGUGUUCAGUCCUCUCUGCAGGUGAGAUGGGGUCUGAGAGUCAAGGCAAGUGUUCAGUCCUCUCUGCAGGUGAGAUGGGGUCUGGGAGUCAAGGCGAGUGUUCAGUCCUCUCUGCAGGACAGAUGGGGUCUGAGAGUCAAGGCGAGUGUUCAGUCCUCUCUGCAGGUGAGAUGGGGUCUGGGAGUCAAGGCGAGUGUUCAGUCCUCCCUGCAGGUGAGAUGGGGUCUGGGAGGGGCAAGUGUUCCAUCUUCCCUGCAGGAGAGAUGGGGUCUGGGAGUCACAGAGUGGGUCCAGUCCUCCCUGCAGGAGAGAUGGGGUCUGAGAGUUGGGGGACGAGGGUCUAGUCCUCCCUGCAGGUGAGAUGGGGUCUGGGAGUCAAGGAGAGUGUUCAGUCCUCCCUGCAGGUGAGAUGGGGUCUGGGAGGGGCAAGUGUUCCAUCUUCCCUGCAGGAGAGAUGGGAUCUGGGAGUCACAGAGUGGGUCCAGUCCUCCCUGCAGGAGAGAUGGGGUCUGAGAGUUGGGGGACGAGGGUCCAGUCCUCCCUGCAGGUUGGGUGUACGAUGUGUCAGCAGAGCAUGCAGAAGUCCUCGCUGGAGUUUCAUAAGGCCAAUGAGUGCCAGGAGCGCCCUGUUGAGUGUAAGUUCUGCAAACUGGACAUGCAGCUCAGCAAGCUGGAGCUCCACGAGUCCUACUGUGGCAGCCGGACAGAGCUCUGCCAAGGCUGUGGCCAGUUCAUCAUGCACCGCAUGCUCGCCCAGCACAGAGAUGUCUGUCGCAGUGAACAGGCCCAGCUCGGGAAAGGGGAAAGAAUUUCAGCUCCUGAAAGGGAAAUCUACUGUCAUUAUUGCAACCAAAUGAUUCCAGAAAAUAAGUAUUUCCACCAUAUGGGUAAAUGUUGUCCAGACUCAGAGUUUAAGAAACACUUUCCUGUUGGAAAUCCAGAAAUUCUUCCUUCAUCUCUUCCAAGUCAAGCUGCUGAAAAUCAAACUUCCACGAUGGAGAAAGAUGUUCGUCCAAAGACAAGAAGUAUAAACAGAUUUCCUCUUCAUUCUGAAAGUUCAUCAAAGAAAGCACCAAGAAGCAAAAACAAAACCUUGGAUCCACUUUUGAUGUCAGAGCCCAAGCCCAGGACCAGCUCCCCUAGAGGAGAUAAAGCAGCCUAUGACAUUCUGAGGAGAUGUUCUCAGUGUGGCAUCCUGCUUCCCCUGCCGAUCCUAAAUCAACAUCAGGAGAAAUGCCGGUGGUUAGCUUCAUCAAAAGGAAAACAAGUGAGAAAUUUCAGCUAGAUUUGGAAAAGGAAAGGUACUACAAAUUCAAAAGAUUUCACUUUUAACACUGGCAUUCCUGCCUACUUGCUGUGGUGGUCUUGUGAAAGGUGAUGGGUUUUAUUCGUUGGGCUUUAAAAGAAAAGGUUUGGCAGAACUAAAAACAAAACUCACGUAUCAUCUCAAUAGAUACAGAAAAGGCUUUUGAUAAAAUUCAACUUGACUUCAUGUUAAAAACCCUCAACAAACCAGGCGUCGAAGGAACAUACCUCAAAAUAAUAAGAGCCAUCUAUGACAAAACCACAGCCAACAUCAUACUGAAUGAGCAAAAGCUGGAGCAUUACUCUUGAGAAGUAGAACAAGGCACUUCAGUCCUAUUCAACAUAGUACUGGAAGUCCUCGCCACAGCAAUCAGGCAAGAGAAAGAAAUAAAAGGCAACCAAAAAGAAAGGAAGUCGAAGUAUCUCUGUUUGCAGACGAUAUGAUUCUAUAUCUAGAAAACCCCAUGAUCUUGGCCCAAAAGCUCCUAGAUCUGAUAAACAACUUCAGCUAACUUUCAGGAGACAAAAUCAAUAUACAAAAUAUGGUAGCAUUUUUAUACACCAACGACAUCCAAGCUGAGAGCCAAAUCAAGAAUGCAAUCCUAUUCACAAUUGCCACAAAAAGAAUAAAAUACCUAGGAAUACAGCUAACCAGGGAGAUGAAAGAUCUCUACAACAAAAAUUACAAAACACUGCUGAAAGAAAUCAGAGAUGACACAAAUGGAAAAACAUUCCAUACUUAUGGAUAGGAAGAAUCAAUAUUGUUAAAAUGGCCAUACUACCCAAAGCAAUUUAUAGAUUCAAUGCUAUUCCUAUCAAACUACCAAUAACAUUCUUCACAGAAUCAGAAAAAAAAAGCAUUAAAAUUUAUUUGAAACCAAAAAAGAGCCCAAAAAGCCAAAGCAAUCCUAAGCAAAAAGAACAAAGCUGGAGGCAUCGCAUUACCCAACUUCAAACUAUACUACAGGGCUACAGUAACCAAAACUGCAUGAUACUGGUACAAAAGCAUGGUGCUGGUACAAAAGCAGACACAUAGAUCAAUGGAACAGAAUAGAGGGCCCAGAAAUAAAGCUACACACCUACAACCAUCUAAUCUUUGACAAAGUUGACAAAAAUACGCAAUGGGGAAAGAAUUCCCCAUUCAGUAAGUGGUACUGGGAUAACUAGCUAGCCAUAUGCAGAGGAUUGAAACUGAACCACUUCCUUACACCAUAUGCAAAAAUCAACUCAAGAUGGAUUAAAGACUUAAAUGUAAAACCCCAAACUAUAAAAACUCUGGAAGAUAACCUAGGCAAUACCAUUCUGGACAUAGGAACGGAAAAAGAUUUCAUGACAAAGAUCCCAAAAAUAAUUGUAACGAAAGCAAAAAUUGACAAAUGGGACAUGAUUAAACAGAAUUACCAUUUGACUCAGCAAUCCCAUUAUUGGUUAUAUACCCAAAGGAAUCUAAAUCAUUCUGUCAUAAAGACAUAUAUACACAAAUGUUCACGGCAGCACUAUACACAAUCGCAAAGUCAGGGAAUCAAACUAAAUGUCCAUCAGUGGUAGAAAGGAUAAAGAAAAUGUGGUGGCAGGGAGUGGUGGCUCAUGUCUGUAAUCCCAGCACUUUGGGAGGCUGAGGCGGGUGGUUCACCUGAGGUCAGGAGUUUGAGACCAGCCUGGCCAACAUGGAGAAACUCCGUCUCCGCUAAAAAUACGAAAAUUAGCCAGGCGUGGUGGCGAGCACCUGUCAUCCCAGCUACUUGGGAGGCCUAGGCGUGAGAAUCGCUUGAACCUGGAAGGUGGUGGUUGCAGUGAGCCGAGAUCCUGCCACUGCACUCCAGCCUGGGCAACCAAGCGAGACUCUGCCUUAAAAAAAAAAAAAAGAAAAUGUGGCACAUAUACACCAUGGAAUACUAUGCAGCCAUAAAAAAGAAUGGGAUCAUGUCCUGUGCAGCAACGUGGAUGGAGCUGGAAGCCAUUAUCCUAAAUGAACUCACUCAGAAACAGAAAACCAAAUACCACAUGUUCUCACUUAUAAGUAGAAGCUAAACAUUGAGUACACAUGGAUACAAAGAAGGGAACCGCAGACACUGGGGCCUACCUGAGGUCGGAGCAUGGAAGGAGGGUGAGGAUCAAAAAACUACCUAUCUGGUACUAUGCUUUUUAUCUGGAUGAUGAAAUAAUCUGUACAACAAACCCUGGUGACAUGCAAUUUACCUAUAUAGCAAGCCUACACAUGUGCCCCUGAACCUAAAAAAAAAGUUAAAAGAAAAACGUUUGGAUUAUUUUCCCUCUUUCGAACAAAGACAUUGGUUUGCCCAAGGACUACAAAUAAACCAACGGGAAAAAAGAAAGGUUCCAGUUUUGUCUGAAAAUUCUGAUUAAGCCUCUGGGCCCUACAGCCUGGAGAACCUGGAGAAUCCUACACCCACAGAACCCGGCUUUGUCCCCAAAGAAUAAAAACACCUCUCUAAAA